GCAGCGGAGCCGAGCCGAGCCCGAGCCCGCGCCGAGCCCUGACACUGUCUGCCCGCCUUCUGGCUCCCCGGGAGCCCAGACUGGUCGGAGCCCGAGCGGUGGCAGCGCGGGGAGCCCCACGCGCCGAAGGGAGCGGACCCGACAGGACGGCCCUAGAGGAGGUGCUGCCGCCACAGUAGCAGGGACCGGAGUCUCGAGCCGCGGCCUCCCGGACCGUGCUGCCCAGGCCAGCUCAGGGACAGCCGGGAGUACGAAAGCCCCACCCUCUGGGGCACCCCGGGAGCGGAGGCGGGAGCGGGGACGCGAGCAACCUCUCCCCCUGUUGGAGAGAAAAGACCCUUACCACUCGGGUGAGGGAAAGAAGAGACCCCUGGAGGGGACGCCUCUCUCCUGCCUAGAGGCGAGGAAGACCCCUGUACUGGCCGGGGAGGAGACCCCCAGAAGUGGAAAGAAGGGAGCUUUCCGUAGGGAAGCAGAGUGAGACCACCCUAGCGCGCCCCCGCCCCUCCAAACACACACUCUCAACAGUUCAGGACUUUGGAGGCAAAGAGAGACGGGGCUGUGCCUGUGGAGUAGGCACCCUCGGCCCACCACUAUUCACAGGAGACAGGAGUCCUUACGUUCAGAAGCCACUCCAGGGAAAGAAGAGGAAUCGGCUUUCAGCCUUCUGGAGAGGGGAAGACCUCCCCCUCAACUUCCUCGUGCCUAGACAGUGGAACGGGGUGGAGCCCCUCCGCUCCUAUCUCCAGCAGACAGAAAGAGCCCUCCACCUCAGAAAGAUCCAGUUUGGGGGGGAGGGGAACUCCCCCAAGGGGGAGGAGACAACUCCUGGUUGGGAGAGGCUCCUCCCCUCCUCCCCCGGGUAACAAGCAGGGUGUGGGGGGUGUGCCACCUUCCCCAAGUAGGACCUCCUUCUCCUCCCCCUCCCCCUCCUCCAACCUUGACUCCUCAUCCUCAGGGGACCCAGUUCCCCUCACCAACUUGGGAGGCUCAGCCUCGUCCAGGAAGAGCCACUGAGGAUGAGAGCCGUCACCUGCCUCUGAAGAGGGGAAUCCCUCCAACCCCAAACUCCAGUACCAGGUGGUUCCCUCCCUUUGCCGGAGGAACCUUGGAGACAGGUCCCUUAGGGAAGUGGAUGUUUUCAUGCUGAGGAAAAGGGUUAUCGGAAAACAGCUGCAUUUUGAGAACAUGCAUACUGUGUAGCAGUGAUUUACACAACCCAACCAGUGAACCCAGAAGUACCAUGGCUUCUGACCUAGAGAGUAGCCUCACCUCCAUAGACUGGCUCCCCCAGCUGACCCUCCGAGCUACCAUUGAGAAGCUUGGAAGUGCCUCCCAGGCUGGGCCUCCCGGGAGCAGCCGCAAGUGUUCACCAGGGUCACCCACAGAUCCUAAUGCCACCCUGAGCAAAGACGAGGCAGCAGUGCACCAGGACGGCAAGCCACGAUACAGCUAUGCCACUCUCAUCACCUAUGCCAUCAACUCCUCUCCAGCCAAGAAGAUGACCCUCAGCGAGAUUUACCGCUGGAUCUGUGAUAACUUCCCCUAUUACAAGAAUGCUGGCAUUGGUUGGAAGAAUUCAAUACGGCACAACCUUUCUCUCAACAAGUGUUUCCGGAAGGUGCCCAGACCUCGGGAUGACCCUGGGAAGGGUUCCUAUUGGACAAUUGACACCUGCCCUGACAUUUCCCGAAAGAGAAGACACCCUCCAGAUGAUGAUCUGUCCCAAGACUCACCAGAACAGGAGGCAAGCAAGAGCCCACGGGGAGGCGUUGCAGGGAGUGGAGAAGCCUCACUGCCUCCUGAGGGGAAUCCGCAGAUGUCACUUCAGAGCCCCACAUCUAUAGCCAGCUACAGCCAGGGCACAGGAUCUGUGGAUGGUGGAGCAGUGGCAGCAGGGGCUUCAGGCCGAGAAAGUGCUGAGGGUCCCCCUCCCCUCUAUAACACCAACCAUGACUUUAAAUUCUCCUACUCAGAGAUCAACUUUCAGGAUCUAAGCUGGUCCUUCCGCAACCUCUAUAAGUCCAUGCUGGAGAAGUCCUCUUCCUCCUCUCAGCACGGCUUUUCUUCUCUCCUGGGGGACAUCCCACCCUCGAACAACUACUACAUGUAUCAGCAGCAGCAGCCACCGCCACCUCAACAGCAGCAGCAGCAGCAGCAGCCGCCACAGCCACCUCCCCAGCAGUCCCAGCCACAGCAGCAGCAGGCACCUGCCCAGGGCCCCUCAGCUGUAGGGGGUGCUCCUCCACUGCACACCCCAAGCACAGAUGGUUGUACCCCACCAGGGGGAAAGCAAGCUGGGGCGGAAGGCUAUGGGCCUCCCCCUGUAAUGGCCAUGCAUCCACCCCCGCUGCAGCAUGGAGGCUACCACCCUCAUCAGCACCAUCCCCACUCCCACCCUGCCCAGCAGCCACCACCUCCACAGCCACAGGCACAAGGCCAGGCUCCCAUCAACAACACUGGCUUUGCCUUUCCUUCUGACUGGUGCUCUAAUAUUGACUCUUUAAAGGAAAGCUUCAAGAUGGUGAAUCGGCUCAAUUGGUCCAGCAUUGAGCAGUCACAAUUCUCAGAACUGAUGGAGAGUCUACGACAGGCAGAGCAGAAGAACUGGACCCUCGACCAGCAUCACAUUGCCAAUCUGUGUGACUCCCUCAACCACUUCCUUACUCAGACUGGUCACGUGCCCCCUCAAGGGGGUACCCACCGCCCACCAGCCCCUGCCCGUAUUGCUGACUCCUGUGCCCUCACCAGUGGCAAACAGGAGUCAGCCAUGAGCCAAGUGGUGAGGACUGACAGCUUCUGCAGAAAGCCUUCAUGCCUGCAGGAGCUACAGAACAGGGCAGGGAAGAGAGAAGGAGGAUGGGAGCAAGGUGAACUCUUAUGGGCACCCACAAGCUCCCCACCUCUACCCUGGCCCAUCACCAAUGUACCCAAUCCCCACCCAGGACUCAGCAGGAUACAAUCGCCCAGCACACCAUAUGGUCCCUCGGCCAUCAGUGCCACCUCCUGGUGCCAAUGAGGAGAUCCCUGAUGACUUCGACUGGGACUUGAUCACUUAGUGCAUCACAGAGUGUGGACAUCAGCCCAGGGCCGCGUGGUGAAAUCUGGCAGUGGGGAAAGAGCAACCCCAGCCCGUCCCUUCCCCCCGUCUGUAUAUAGACAUAUAUCCUCUUUUUGUUCUUUCUCUGUCAGAGAAGCCACUGCAAGAUGCUGCCGAAGAUAACCCUCUCUUUCCUGCCUCAUUCUUCUCUCUUCCUUCCUGUUUUUUCCUAGUUCUUUUAUUAUUAUUCUUAUAUUAUUAUUAUUAUUAUUGGUUAUAUACUGUCCAUAGUCUCCUGUCCCUACAUCAUGGAUCAUGUCCACCUUUUGCUAAUUUAAAAUCAUCAGGCUGGAAGAUGAAGCCAUGAUAGCUACAGAGAAAGGUUUUAGACUCCAGUUUACCUUUCUCUUGGAGAAACUCAAUGCUAAUCCCACCUUUUGGCCCUAAAUUGUUUUUUGUUCCCAUCAGUUUCAGGCCAGGACUGGAGAGGCCACAUUACCAAGUAGAAAGGGUCUGAAACAUUACUUGGCAGCCAAGAAUUUGGAGGUUUUAAAAUGGUGCUAAUUCUGUCCUCUGAGGUCUUCCUUGUCCCUUUAUACCUUCAAUCCUUACUUCUGCCAGUCUGUAUUUCCUAUCAAGGGUGAAAGUGAUGAUGGUGGUGCAGGAGGGUGACAAUAAAAUCCUAGUGGAAUUGGAGACCAUUGGAAGGGAUGGAAUAUAAGUCAGUGUGAAACUGAGUAUACACUGCCAUGUUACAUCAGUGUCCAUUGGCUUGUUUUGAGCCUGUUCUCUAAGAAGAUAGGAUUGGUUUUAGCCCAAACUCUGCUUCUAUGGUAGGGCAUGAGGACAACUAUUCAGCAUGGUUUUAGCUUCUUGGAGAUGAUUCCAACUUAACUAUUUUGGCUUUUUAAACAUAAUUUUCUCUGAAAAUUAAUUGUGGCUCUUAUUUGCAUUUACGAAUGAUCUUCCCAUCCCUUUUUCCCAUUCAGCAAAUAUUAGUUUGUCCUCCUUUAAUUGUUUGCCCAAAUCUUCCACCCAUCUUUUUUCUUCCCUCAUUUUCUGGGAUUCUCAAGAAAGAAAAAGUAACCCAUUAUCACUCUGAGUUUCGUCGUGCCCUGAGACAUGAUGGGAAUCUCAUUCCCACCUCUCAUAGCAGAGCCAAACCUUUAGUGUUGGUGGUAGGAGGAUGGGGAGAGGAAAAAAGAGCUGGCAAAGAAAUGGAUAGGGAAUAUUUUAGUUCUUUAAAUAUAUAGGCAGAUGCUUCUCUUGGAAUCCAGAUCAUCUGGCUGAAGCUUUUGCAAGUAGGCUUUGAGGGGUGAAGGAGAUUGGUGGAGGAGAGUAAAUAAUCUAGAGGCAAGAGUUCAGUGAGGGCCAAGGGGGACCCCCAGAAAAAGGUAUGGAGCUAACUCAUCUCUUUUACAAGGGGUGGCCAUGACUUACUGUUGCAAAGUACUCAGUGUAUAUUUAAUGUUGAUUGUUGAAUUUUAGUUACGAGAGGGAAGAACAAUUUUACUUCUGUCCUUAUUUCACUUGCUGAAAAGCUGUGGGACAAAAUGUAUGGAAUAGACAAGGCCACUUUCUUUGUGAUUUCUGCUUUUCAUGCAUAUUAUUUUAUUUACCCAUAAUUUCCAAGAGGUUUGGCGUUCCGCUCUCCUGCUUUUUUCUUUCAUCCACCCCUUUCCUUUUUUUGGAAGGGGGUUAUAUAUGAGAGUUCAUUGAAGAAGUCCAGUGAGGCUGAAGUAAAGGGGCAAGAUAGGGCAGUUAACUAAAGAGCACUUUAUUUCUUUGAAGCCUUUCUAAGAAAGAAAUGGGGGUGCGAGUGGCUUGAAUCUCCCAUGAUGUUGGAGGGCACUUAGUGGGGUUGAAGUAUGACAUAAUAUUUCCCAUUGGGGAAAGGAGAAUUUCUCUUAGAGGGUGGCAAAAUGCCUUUGCCCAGUGUCCCUAUUUUAGGCAUCUUUUCCUUCCUUAUUCCUUCCAGUCAGGGUGUGUCCUAUACAAAACUUCCCAUCAGUUCUCCUCAAUAUUCCCCAUUUGUAAAUGAUCACUUCUCUUUUCUAAACCCUUUUCCUGUUCAGAUCCAUACAGGAUUUGCAAGGGUAGGAUCAUACAUGCAAAUGCCCCUUGUUCAUCUGUGUCUUCUGCAAACUAGUCUCAUGAAGAAUUCUGGCGUGCAGCCAGGGUAGCUGAAGUUUGGGUCUGGGACUGGAGAUUGGCCAUUAGGCCUCCUGAGAUUCCAGCUCCCUUCCACCAAGCCCAGUCUUGCUACGUGGCACAGGGCAAACCUGACUCCCUUUGGGCCUCAGUUUCCCCUCCCCUUCAUGAAAUGAAAAGAAUACUACUUUUUCUUGUUGGUCUAGCAUUGCUGGACACAAAGUGUAGUCAUUAUUGUUGUAUUGGGUGAUGUGUGCAAAACUGCAGAAGCUCACUGCCUAUAAGAGGAAAUAAGAGAGAAAGUGGAGGAGAGGGACAAAAGGAGUAAUUAUUUGGUAUAGAUCCACCCAUCCCAACCUUUCUCUCCUCAGUCCCUGCUCCUCAUGUUUCUGGUUUGGUGAGUCCUUUGUGCCACCACCCAUAAUGCUUUGCAUUGCUGCAUCCUGGGAAGGGGGUAUAUGGUCUCACAAGUUGUUGUCAUUGUUUUUUUGCAUGCUUUCUUAAUAAAAAAAAAAAAAGAAUGUUUACAGUUUUA